CUGGCUGGGUUAGGCCAGAAGGGUGUCCCUGGCGCAGGUCUCCCGCGGAGGGCAGAACUAGAACCAGGUUCCCGGCCGUUUCCGACCACACGGAUGGGGCGGACCCAUGUGAGCCCUCACUAAUUGCAGGGGACGAAGCUGGGCAUAUGGGGAAACUGGGGGUUUCCAGGCGAGUGGACGGUGGGAUGGGAUCCGACGUGCACACCCACGUUUCAGGCUACUGUUUCCACCUCACGUCGCCGCCCCUUUGCUUAUGGACUCUUGCAGAGUUGGAUUGAGCUCGGACUGUGUGACAUAGUGGUUGUUGCAGAAGCCCCAGGGCCACUUUCUGACUAGUACCUUGGGCACCUGACGUCAUCCCUUUGAGUCUCAGUGUCCUCUUCUGUAAAGUGAGGGCGCUUUACCUGAGGGGAUUGCUGUAAGGUUGGAAUGAACCUGCAUGUGUGAGUCAUGUGGGAAGGGAACAGUCAAUGGGGCCUGGGGUUCUCUUGGAGAGCUGGUAACCAGCCUCGUCCCUGAGGCAACAGCCAGAGGGCGCCUGUAGUUUCCCCACGCAUGGCUGUUAGCAGGGCCUCUGCAGGAUCUCCUGUGGGAGGUCCCUACUUCUCACUACAAUCUUUAGGGCCUUUGGAGGAUUUCCUAUGGAAGGUCCCCACUUCUCACCACAACAUUCUGGGUUAAAAUGUCCUUGGUAGGAAGAUGGGGCUGAAGCUAGAUUUUCUUGCUUGCAUUACAAGCUUCUGAACCAAGGACUUCAAUGUCACCUGGACUUGGAUUCACAUCCCAGCUCCUUCCCUUCCUAGCUUUAAGACUGUGUAACCUUGGGCAAAUCCCUUAACCGCUUUAAGCCUUAACUGUUUCAUCUGUAAAAUGGGACUAACAGUACCUACCUUCCACAAGCGUCAAGAAUUAAAUCAGGCCUGGCGCGGUGGCUCACGCCUGUAAUACCAACAAUUUGGGAGGCCGAGGCAGGCGGAUCACAAGGUCAGGAGAUCGAGACCGUCCUGGCUAACACAGUGAAACACCGUCUCUACUAAAAAUACAAAAAUUAGCUGGGCGUGGCGGCGUGCACCUGUAGUCUCAGCUGCUGGGGAGGCUGAGGCAGGAGAAUGGCGUGAACCCGGGAAGCAGAGCUUGCAGUGAGCCAAGAUCGUGCCACUGCAUUCCAGCCUGGGCGACAGAGCGAGACUCCAUCUCAAAAAAAAAAAAAAAGAAUUAAAUCGGACAUUGUAGGUAGAGCACUUAAUAGUUGGCAUUCAGCGGCAGCAGUUACUGUUAUGUUAGCAUGUGGAGUGUCUGAGUGUGUGCACUUUGGCUCGAACAGCCUUUUGACAGUGGCACAGUUGGUGCUUGUGUAAGAUAGCAGGGCAGAGAAGUCAAAACCCUCGGUUUUCUAGUCAAACUGGUGGGCCACAACAGUGGUGACCUAAGUCUAAUGAGUCUUUCACUGAACAAGGCAGAUUGAAUCUCCAGGCGAGGACCAAGAGUCUGGGGCUCAGCUGCCUCAACAUUUUUGGGCAUAGAAGGCUGUACAAUACAAACAGCCUUUGUUGUAAGAGCAAGGAACCAUUCAGGGAAGGCACCAUGUGGUAAGGAAUAGUGGCCAGAAUUGGAUUCAGAACAAAACAAGAGAAUAGUGUUUGUCUUUAAGUGGAGCCUUGGACUCAAAAUAGGACCUGAGCUCUGUGGAUAAUUUCUUUUUUUUUUUUUUUUUUGGAGUUGCUCUGUUGCCCAGGCUGGAGUGUCGUGGCAUGUUCUUGGCUCACUACAACCUCUGCCUCCUGUGUUCAAGUGAUUCUCGUAUCUCAGCUUCCCUAGUAGCUGGGAUUACAGGCGCCUGCCACCAGUCCUGGCUAAUUUUUUUGCAUUUUUAGGGGAGACAGGGUUUCGCCAUGUUGGCCAGGCUGGUCUUGAACUCCUGACCUCAAGUGAUCCACCCACCUCGAACUCCCAAUGUGCUAGGGAUUUCAGGUGUGAGCCACUGCGCCUGGCCCUUGUGGAUACUUUCUAGGUGAUUUGAGGAGGAAAGGCACAGCCAUGUCUCCUAAAGUUAACAAGCACUAAGCUUUCCCAAGUAGUGAAAUGUCAAGCCUCUGCUUCUGUCACUUAUUUGUUCAUUCAGCAGAAAGUCACUGAGAGCCUUCUGUACACCAGGCACAGUGCUGGGCAGUGAAAGAGACAGACAUGUCCCUGGAUCCAGGGAGGAGAUGACCAAGUGAUGGCUGUCAGGCCCAGACCUUGCUGUUUGUCUGCAGCCUCUUCCCUCAGGCAACUUGUUCUCUAUCAGGAGAAAUGAAAUAAUUAUUAUCUGGAGAGGCAGGUGGGGGCGCUGCUCCUAGAAGACAAGGACAGCCUGGUAGAGGUUCUAGCUUGAUCAUGUGAGCAGUGGAAACCAUUUUAAGUUGGAGGUUAACAGGACCAAAAUAGCAUUUAAAAAAUGGCUUAUGGCCACUGUGAAGCCAGUUUCACCAGCAUCACUUGCCCAUGCUGGGCUGCCACCCAGCUAAUUCCUGGUCCUGCUCAUUUAGCCCAGCUCAGCUCACAUCACUUCCUCCAGAAACUAGACAAGGGUAGAGCCCCUGACCAUCUUCACAGCAUUAGUCCUGAUAGCUGAAUCUUACGUCACUUGUUAACAUCUGUGACCUGUGCAGGGAGAAUGGCAGGGCUGAGUUUCACCUACAUUGUUUCCCCAAUACCUACAGCAGAGCCAAGCACAGUGGGAACUUUCAGAAAGCACUGGUUGAAGGAACACUGGAAUCCCUGGGACUUACUGCGUAGCAUGUAGUAGUUGCUCCUGUAGAAAAGUUUCACCUUAUGAAGAAUAGCAGGUAAAAUACAAGCCUGGACCACUUCCCGUGUGGUAUGCAGGGAACGGUUGAUGGGGCAAAGGGCCUUGGGCUAUAUAGCCCUAGGAAUUUCAGAGAUCCUGAUGAUGGCUCUGGGAUCCUCCGUCUCCUGGAUCCUGCAUUUUUCUCUGCAGGCUCUGAUGGUGGUGUCUGGUAGAAGGUUACUCACAGCUCUGCUGCAGGCUCAGAAGUGGCCCUUUCAACCCUCCAGAGACAUGAGACUAGUGCAGUUCUGGGCACCCCACCUGGUGGGGCCUCACUUGGGCCUGGAGACAGGGAAUGGUAGAGGGAUUAUCAACCUCAAUGCCUUUGACCCCACACUCCCAAAGACAAUGACGCAGUUCCUAGAGCAGGGAGAGGCCACCCUCUCAGUGGCAAGAAGAGCCUUGGCUGCCCAGUUGCCAGUCCUACCACGGUCGGAGGUAACCUUCCUGGCUCCAGUCACAUGGCCAGAUAAGGUGGUGUGUGUGGGCAUGAAUUAUGUGGACCACUGCAAAGAACAGAACGUGCCCGUGCCCAAGGAGCCCAUCAUCUUCAGCAAGUUUGCCAGCUCCAUCGUGGGGCCCUAUGAUGAGGUGGUCCUCCCACCACAGAGCCAGGAGGUAGAUUGGGAAGUGGAGCUGGCCGUGGUCAUUGGAAAGAAAGGCAAGCACAUCAAGGUGAAGUGGAAAAGGUGUUGGUGUCACCCAUGAUCUAUCCUCCUGUAUGGCCAAAUCCCCUGCCCCCAUAGGCCACAGAUGCCAUGGCCCACGUGGCCGGCUUCACUGUGGCUCAUGACGUGAGUGCUCGUGACUGGCUAACAAGAUGCAAUGGGAAACAGUGGCUGCUGGGAAAAA